AGUAUCUGUGGGUACCCGGAGCACGGAGAUCUCGCCGGCUUUACGUUCACCUCGGUGUCUGCAGCACCCUCCGCUUCCUCUCCUAGGCGACGAGACCCAGUGGCUAGAAGUUCACCAUGUCUAUUCUCAAGAUCCAUGCCAGGGAGAUCUUUGACUCUCGCGGGAAUCCCACUGUUGAGGUUGAUCUCUUCACCUCAAAAGGUCUCUUCAGAGCUGCUGUGCCCAGUGGUGCUUCAACUGGUAUCUAUGAGGCCCUAGAGCUCCGGGACAAUGAUAAGACUCGCUAUAUGGGGAAGGGUAAGCCUUAGAACCCACAGCCCAUGGCCUCCCUGCUUCCAGCCCCAUUCCUGGCCUUGCCCAGUCCUGUCCUCUCUGGGUGGCACUUGCACUUGCAGGUUUAUGGCAGGUAAACCUGCUGUGACCCAUGAUGUUGAUGGAAGCAGUGCACCACCUUGUGGACAGGAAAGUUGGUGUGUGGAUUCCGGGGUUCCCGAGCCUGCAUGCUCUGGGUCGAGAGUUCCAAUGCUUGCUUCUAUUGCAGUUUGUUCCCAAUCUGCGAAAUACUCCUUCACGGUUAGGACAGGAACCCAAGCAUGAGAACAGGGCCUGUUAACUAAAGAAAAGUUUCCCCAUCUCCCAGGAGGGUUCUGUGGGCCCUCCAGAGAUCAUCAGCCUCUUCACGGGCUAGAAAGGAUCCAGGGAAGGUCUAACCAAUGACCUGCCCUGAAUGGUGAGCUGCAGGUGUGUCAUUUAGUGUGAUUUUCCUGUUGACUGACUCAUAGGAGCCCUGCUCUGUGGCAGAGCUAGCCUCUGGCUGUAUUCAAAUUGACUUAGUGUGUGUGCAACAUUGACCUUUCUAGAGAUAGAACAUGUGGCCAAAUUACAGAAAAGCACAUAGGGCUAGAUCACGCAUUCUCAGUGGGGCACCCGGAAAACUCCAAAAAGGCUGCAGGGAGGGGACAAUGAUGAAAUCAGGUUGUGAAACACUGGGCUGGUGUCGCAGUGGUGGUGCUGGGUGUUCAGUCCCGCUUUAAUGCUGUAAGAAGCACUCUACACACACGAACAUGUUACCAUUUGACCGUUGUUUAAUGGCGUACGUGGGGACUUAGCCGGAGCAGGAUGAUGCUGUGCCUUGAUGGUAAUGAGUGCUCAGUAAGUAAGCAUUUGUGGAAGAUUGAACGCAUGGCCCCUGAAAUGCUCUCCUCUGCUUUCCUGCCCCCUCACUGUCUCUCACUCGCAGUCCUUAAUCACCGGUUCUCUUCUGAGUCUCUCUCAUUUUUCCUUCUUCAUCCUCUGCUGGGCAGGCGUCUCCAGACCCAUUAAGUAUAUUAAUGAGUUCCUGGCACCAGCCCUGUGCACUCAGGUAACUGAUUGAACAGCCUUUAGUCUGCAGUUGGCGUUUCCAGUGCAUGGUCUUGCAAACUAACCUCCAGUCAGAUCGUUCUGAGCCAGCUGCUGUUUUGUGUGGCUCUAACCCUCUGGGGUCCUAGGUAGGAGCACUCAGACUGGGCCGGAAAGUCCUCCGAUUCUGGGGGGAAAGGGGAGAGGGGGAAGAGGUCCCACAGAAGGUCCCUUGGUGGGCUUCCGCGUCGGCCUCAACAGUGGUUCUCUCUAACAAUGCUGCUCAAGCCUGUUUUAAAGUUAAUGUCAGUAAUUUGAUUUGAUUGUUCCUUCCAGGUGUCUCAAAGGCUGUUGAGCACAUCAAUAAAACUAUUGCGCCUGCCCUGGUUAGCAAGAAACUGAACGUCACAGAACAAGAGAAGAUUGACAAACUGAUGAUCGAGAUGGAUGGAACAGAAAAUAAAUCUAAGUUUGGUGCGAACGCCAUUCUGGGGGUGUCCCUUGCCGUCUGCAAAGCUGGUGCCGUUGAGAAGGGGGUCCCCCUGUACCGCCACAUCGCUGACUUGGCUGGCAACUCUGAAGUCAUCCUGCCAGUCCCGGCGUUCAAUGUCAUCAAUGGCGGUUCUCAUGCUGGCAACAAGCUGGCCAUGCAGGAGUUCAUGAUCCUCCCAGUCGGUGCAGCAAACUUCAGGGAAGCCAUGCGCAUUGGAGCAGAGGUUUACCACAACCUGAAGAAUGUCAUCAAGGAGAAAUAUGGGAAAGAUGCCACCAAUGUGGGGGAUGAAGGCGGGUUUGCUCCCAACAUCCUGGAGAAUAAAGAAGGCCUGGAGCUGCUGAAGACUGCUAUUGGGAAAGCUGGCUACACUGAUAAGGUGGUCAUCGGCAUGGACGUAGCGGCCUCCGAGUUCUUCAGGUCUGGGAAGUAUGACCUGGACUUCAAGUCUCCCGAUGACCCCAGCAGGUACAUCUCGCCUGACCAGCUGGCUGACCUGUACAAGUCCUUCAUCAAGGACUACCCAGUGGUGUCUAUCGAAGAUCCCUUUGACCAGGAUGACUGGGGAGCUUGGCAGAAGUUCACAGCCAGUGCAGGAAUCCAGGUAGUGGGGGAUGAUCUCACAGUGACCAACCCAAAGAGGAUCGCCAAGGCCGUGAACGAGAAGUCCUGCAACUGCCUCCUGCUCAAAGUCAACCAGAUUGGCUCCGUGACCGAGUCUCUUCAGGCGUGCAAGCUGGCCCAGGCCAAUGGUUGGGGCGUCAUGGUGUCUCAUCGUUCGGGGGAGACUGAAGAUACCUUCAUCGCUGACCUGGUUGUGGGGCUGUGCACUGGGCAGAUCAAGACUGGUGCCCCUUGCCGAUCUGAGCGCUUGGCCAAGUACAACCAGCUCCUCAGAAUUGAAGAGGAGCUGGGCAGCAAGGCUAAGUUUGCCGGCAGGAACUUCAGAAACCCCUUGGCCAAGUAAGCUGUGGGCAGGCAAGCCCUUCGGUCACCUGUUGGCUACACAGACCCCUCCCCUCGUGUCAGCUCAGGCAGCUCGAGGCCCCCGACCAACACUUGCAGGGGUCCCUGCUAGUUAGCGCCCCACCGCCGUGGAGUUCGUACCGCUUCCUUAGAACUUCUACAGAAGCCAAGCUCCCUGGAGCCCUGUUGGCAGCUCUAGCUUUGCAGUCGUGUAAUUGGCCCAAGUCAUUGUUUUUCUCGCCUCACUUUCCACCAAGUGUCUAGAGUCAUGUGAGCCUCGUGUCAUCUCCGGGGUGGCCACAGGCUAGAUCCCCGGUGGUUUUGUGCUCAAAAUAAAAAGCCUCAGUGACCCAUGAGAAUA